ACUGGCUCCAGCCUUAGGGAAGGUUUUGGCCGUGGGUUUUGUUGGCACGUACCAUUUUGCUGAAAGACAGAGCACCUUGAGGACGUUAUCCCUAAAAUGAGAGAGGACUGGGAUUGAAAGGCUGACUACAGAAAUGGCUGCUGCCCAGACGCCCUCAAAAGCCAAGGAUCCUCAGAGUUGGUUAUAAAAUAUUUAAGGGCGAGAAAAGGAUCGCAGGAGCCAGGCCCUGAGAUGAGCUUGGAGUCCCUGUUUCAGCACAUCAUCUUCACCGAGCAUCAGGCGGAGGAGAGUCGCCGUUUGAUGCGAGAAGUAAGGUCGGAAAUAACCAGAUGUCGUGAAAAAAUUAAGAAAGCAACGGAGGAGCUGAAUGAAGAGAAAAUCAAGCUGGAAUCUAAGGUUCAACAGUUUUUUGAAAAAUCCUUCUUCUUACAGCUUUUGAAAGCUCAUGAAAAUGCUUUAGAAAAACAGUACAGUGAAAUUACAAACCAUAGGAAUAUGCUUCUUCAAACCUUUGAGGCUAUAAAGAAACAAAUGAUAGAGGAGGAAGACAAAUUUAUUAAGGAAAUUACAGACUUUAAUAAUGAUUAUGAAAUAACAAAGAAAAGAGAGCUUUUGAUGAAAGAAAAUGUCAAGAUUGAAAUAUCUGACUUAGAAAACCAAGCAAACAUGUUGAAAAGUGAAAUGAAGUCAAUGGAACAUGAUAGUAGCCAGUUAAAUGAACUUCAAAAACAAAAGAGUGAAUUGAUACAAGAAUUAUUUACUCUCCAAAGAAAACUUAAAGUUUUUGAAGAUGAAGAGAAUGAAUCCAUUUGUACUACCAAAUAUCUAGAGGCAGAAAAAAUAAAAAUCAGUGAAAAGCCUCAAAAUGAUACAGAAUGCUUAAGGUAACUAAAAGGGUGAGUGGUCACCACCUAAUUCUGAUAGGCAUGAGAAGUCAUACAGAACCUGUAGUCCAUUUGAAGUGAAGAGAUGGAUGAGCACGUGUUGAUGGAAUGGUGGGAAUAUCUCUACCAUUUUAUUUGAAAAAUAAAUUUAUUAAAAAGAAGGCUUAUGUACAUUUCAAUAGCAGCAUCCAUAGUAUAUUGUAACUCUCCACUUAACUUUCCAUUUACUCUUUAAAAAUAUUUAUUACAAGGGUUUUUAUACAUGUGUAAAUAUAUGAUGCUUAAAAUUAGUAAUUUAUCUUUCCUUAUUAAGCAUUCCUUUAGAUUUCUCAUUUACUAUUAAAUUCCUAAAAGUUCAGACAGAACACAGUGAACUUCCAUAUACAUAUGUGCUGCAUAAUGACAUUUCAAUCAACAGCAUAUCACAUAUCUAAGAGUGGUCCCAUAAGAUUAUAAGACUGCACUUUUUAUUCCACCUUUUCUAUGUUUAGAUACACACAUACUUACCAUUGUGUUUCAGUUGCCUACAGUAUUCAGUACAGUAACAUGUGGUACAGGUUUGUAACCUAUGAUCAUCUGCUAUACCCUAUAGCCUAGGUGUCUGGUGUGCUAUCCAAUCUAGGUUUGUGUAAGUUCACUCUAUGAUAUUUAUACAAUGACAAAAUCACCUAACUAUGCAUUUCUCACAAUAUUUUCCUGUUGUUAAACGAUGUAUGACUGAAUAGGGUAUUUCACCAUCCACCCUUAUUAUAAAUAUUAUAUUUUUAUUCCCUAGUGGUCCUUAAAAUAAUAUAUGUAAACUAUAUGUAAUUUCUAAAGUAUACUAAUAUAAUGAGCACCUGUGAACUAAAUAUGAGCUAAAUAUGAGCUAAAAAUAAUCAUCCAUGAAAUAAACUAGAAUAUUACCGAUAACUUGCAUUAGCUAUGGCUUCUCUUUUAUUCCAUACUCCCUUCAUUACCCCAGAUAUCGUUGAUGUCCUAUAUUGUAUUUCAUUUUCUUGUGCAUGUCGUUCUACAAUGUGAUUCAUUUACUUGUGUAUAUAUAAUUUUCUUUAUAGUAUUAUAUAACUAACUUUAGUUUACAGCAUGCAUUUAUCAUCUAACCUAUACAUACAUGCACAAUCUAUUGGUUAUUUGUAUUUGUUUUUGAGUUCUGUAAAAAUUAUAUUAUACUAUCUGGGAUUUGUAUUUUAUUCAAUGUUUUUUCUAAGAUUUACCCACGUUGGUGAGUGUAGAUGUAUGACCAUAGCAUAUUUUUUUCUCUUUUUAAUGGACAUUUGGUUUGUUUCAAGAUUUUGGUAUCACCAGCAGUGCUGCUGGUGCACAUAUGCAAGAGUUGUUCCAGGAUAGAUGCCUGUUGGAAUUGCUGAGUGUGGGGCAUGCGAAUGUUGAACUUCACAAGAUGACGACAGACUAUUUUCCAGUGUGAUUAAGCCAGUUUAUAUUCUCAUUAGCACAUUAUGAAAUUUCCUGUUGAUCUCCAUCCUCUUCAAUGCUUUUUAAAGACUUUUUAGUUUUUGCCAAUCUUGUGGACAUAAGAUGGUAUUUCAUGAUCUCUAAUGGCCUUGUCCUGACUACGUAUAUGGUUGAGCAUCUUUUGCAUCUGUUUAUGAUCCAUGCAUUUUUUUCUGUAAAGUAACUCUUAUUUUUCUACUAGAUUGUUUGAGUAAUUUGUCUUUUUCCUAUUAAUUUCCAGAAGUUUUAAAGUUUUGCUCUUUCAGUAGUUGUGAAUUUUGUCUGUUAAUGAAUUAAAAAUAUCUUCUCCAA